UAAGAUGUUGUCCCAGAGACCAAAAUUGACUGAAGGGAAUGAGAGAGGUCUUUGAAAACAGGUCACAAUGUGAAAAGCACUUUGUCUCCACUUUCAUAAAUGAAACUUUUAAUUCCAUUUACCUAACUUCCCCCUGCAAGGAGAUAUUUGAGUUUUAUAAGUGAAGCAUUUGAUGUGAUUAAGUUUAGCAACGUAUGUGAAAAAGGAAAGGAGACUUCUGUAAAGAAUACUUUGAAAUGAGGUAUACUCCAACAGAUGGUUUUCAGUCUUACCAAAUGGGGAAAAAUGAUAAUGUGACCUAGCAAUUUACGUAGAGUUUAGUCAUGGAUUAUUCUUGAAAAACCAGUACUCAGUGUAUUGGGUCGUUGUGGAUUUUUAUUUGUUCAUUUUCCAGAAUACGUAUUGGUCUUAUUUAUAAUUUAAGAGAAGGAAUCUUUUAAAAAGAAUUUGGUGGGAGUGGUUGUAAGUCUGACUGGAGACUGUGUUUAGAGUUUCAGCUGCAUUAUACCUUAAUGCUGUAGAGAUAGAGACUGAAAUAUAAGCUCACUGCGUUCUGCAGCAGGGAGCUUGUCCAAACGUGUGCACUUUCCUGUAUAAUAUGCUUGUUUAAAUGUUGAAGACAUGCAUUAUUUUGUUUUUUACUCUAUUUUGAUUUAGGGGAAAAGGACUUCUGUUAAUUACCUAAUUAAAAGUGGUAUUUCGCUUAUUACUAGAUUUCCAACUGAAGAAGGCAUUGCUAUUAAAUGUGCAGGAAACACAUAUCAGCUUUCUCUUUGGUUUUCAGCUGGCCAAAUUUAACUGGAGAUGUGUAACUUUCUCAGUGAUAGACAUGGAUUUAAUUAUUAGUAAUAGAACUGUAAUGGAAGAAAGUUAAAUUUAUUUGAUUAGGUAUCUGCAUUAUAAAUGUUUGAACUUGGAAGUCAUAUUUCUUCUUCAAAAGCAGACAUCUUUCAUGCUGUUAAUGUUUAUACAUUUUAGUGCUUGGAUAAAGCUAUUCUGACACACUCAAUUAGUUCUUUCAAAAAUGCAUCUCUUUGCUGUCCCUCCCCCUCCCCCUCCCCCUCAAAAGUUCUAGAAGCUGUGGGAAAAGUUCAGUUGUCUAUCUACUGAACGUAGUCCAAGGAAUACCCGUGGGUUUGUUCACUGCUCGGGGAGCUGGACGUGUGCCGCUCUGACUUCCUUUGCACAUCCUUGCUUCCCUGAAUUUGCAUUUAUUGCCUAACUAGCAUCCCGCAAAAAGGCCUUUCCUGGCUGCCUGCGAAUUGGCACCUUGGAGCUUCACUUCCAGCAUUGUUAAUGGCUAAACGUGAAGAACUAAUUUUAUUACUGUAUUUAGCUCACAGGGCCUUGGAAGCGGCCCCUACUCUGUUGUUGGGAGCUGCAUCUCAUUUAGAGUUGCAUUUUUCAAGUGAAUUGUAGUGUCAGGCUGUGCAUCCGUUGUGGGGUCUGAGUGGGUGAUGGUUGGAAUACAUCUCCCCGUGUAUGAGAGGCACCGAGGGAUGUGGAGGUUCUCGGAGGCAGAUGGAGGUGGGGGCUGUGGACAAGCCUCUGUUUGUGCAGCAGUGAUUAUUUGGUUGUUCGACUGUUUGGUUAGGUUCCCCUUGGGCUGGUCGCUAACUGGUGGCAUGAGCUGACAGUGUAGCUGUUCCCUUCUUCUCCCUCCCCUCCUGGGGGCUCUCAUCCUCAGUCCUUCCACCUGACUGGCCGAAAGUGUAGUGGCAGCAGCCUAUUACGGGAAUGUAUCUAGGGGCCAUAGAGGAGACAGCAUUUUUCAAAUUCAAGCUCUGGCCUCAGUUUUCUCUGGUCCCAGGAACCAGUGAGUUUGGGAGUGGGGCAGGACAUUCUCUUUGAUAGAGGAAUGACCUCUGCCCUCAGUUAAGACCACCCUCCCACCCACCAUUGGAUGAGAACUAUCAGAAUCGUUCGAUUUUCAGGAAUUUUGAAAAGGCACAAACCUAUUGUAAGAAAAGAAUCAUGUCAAAUGUUUACAUUUAUGAAUAAUUAAUAAAAUUAACCUUAUGGGAGGAGGAGGAAGAAAGAACAACUUUUACUAUGACUUUAGAAUGUCUCCUGUUCUUUAAAAAGUAUCUUUAUUUUAAAAUUAAUUUUUCUAACUGAAGAAUAUUUUAGGGGAAUGACUUAAAUAGCUAUAAGGAAGGAUAUAUUUAUAGGGGCUAUAAAUGCAUCAUUUGUAUUUGAAAUUUCUAGCAUCCACUACAGUGUACGAAGUGUAUUUUAGAUGGACUGGUAAAAACCAGCAGUUGCAACUGUCUGUUUUGCAUUCCUUAUGCUCUGCAUCUGGCCACACGUGACUUGAACAGCUGAAGCUUCUCUUUCCAAAGCUAGAGCCAUCAUCGUAUUUAUGUCUAGCCUGAGAUGUUUUCCGAUGGUAUACAUUCGAAUUGUAAAGCAGUGUAAUUUGUGGCUCUCAACAUGCCUUAAAAGUCAUUUCCAAAAAAGAUCUGGCAUUUAAUCUUUAAUUCAAAUGGUACUGAAAAUUACAAAGCAGGAGUAAUUAGAAAUGCAACUAUUUUUAGAAAGCAAACAUGUAAAUAUAUGUUAAGUGAUGACUAAAACACAAGCAGGAGAGUAGGAAAAAUUAUUUAAAAGACAACUAUAGUAGGUUUAGAUACAUCUUACCAUAUACUGUAUUUUAACUCUGUGUUAAUUCUGGUAGAUUUACUUCGUAUUCCUGUUUCUGUACCUUCCCCCCGAACCUUGGUCAGGAAGUAAGUAAAGUCUAUAGAAUCUCAGAAUUUACUGGGCCGAGAAGAGAUGUAUAUCGUAUGUAAUUGUGAAAUCCAGACAGUUCCUCAACUGAGUGGUGAAAAUGGGAUGAAAUCUUAGUGUGUUUUGUUAUCUUCAAGGCAGAGGGAAUCUGGUGUUUUUUUUUUUUUUUCCUUCAAAACCAGGUAGACAACGUCUCUCACCGCCCUGGGGAGUUGCUGGUGCUGGCUCAGCCUCCAGGAUACAGCUGUCCUGUUAUUUUCUUGCUUUUUUAGGAGAUGGUGUGCGUAGAGGAAGAUGUGGUGUUAGUUUUCAGGACACAGUUAAAGACAGGCUUAAAAAAUCAAGGUUCUCUAUUAAAACUAUAAUUUCUUGUUAAUGGCUAAGAAUUAAAAAUUUUUCAGCGCUAUUAACACUUGAAGAACUCUCUAAUCCCCCACUCUUCCCAUGUGAAAGUAAAGGACAUUUGUUUAGGAAUUUUUUUGUUUCAGAAAAGGGCAACAUGUGUCUGUCUUUGCCAUAUGGUACUAUUUAACCUAUAUUGCAUGAGCUGACAAGACACUGUGUUUGGGCAUUGAUUUAUUUUAGCAUUCGAGAAUGUUCUUUGAAAUUUAGUACAGUAAAUGAUGCAUUGAAAGUUGUACAGAAUGGUCGUUUGUGGCUUUAGCAGAUUCUUUCUCAGUUGAUACUUAAGGGUGUAGUGAACAAGUUUCACUUUUUUUCCACCGAUACAAUUUUUGUGAGAAAUAGUUUGCCAUUCAAUGCUGAGUGACUGUUAAUUCAGGAAAACACAGACUUGAAUAUAAGUAGUUAAGACUUCUGGGGGUCACAAAUAAGGCUAAGAGUUGGGCAGGUCAGAAAGAGAAGAUUCACUGUUUAGUUCCUGAUUAUUCUGGUGAUUUUAACCUAGAGCAAAAAAGUAUGUUUAUUAUUAUUAUUAUUUUUGUCAAAAAGACUCAGCUUUUGUCCCCAUCUUUUUUUUUUUUUUUUAAAGAAAUGAGUUAAUGAACAAAUGGACAAUCCUAUUUAAUAGUUCCCCUGAGCUUCUGUGGUGCGGCCCUGGAAUUAUCUACAGGCAGAACUGAGAUGUUUUCACUUAGGCUGUGUUUUGUUUACACAUGCUGGUUUGGGUUUUUGGGUAGACCUGUGUUGAAUUCACAGGGUGGCUCUUAUGCCAUGUUGCAGGAAUUUAUUAGUAUGGAACCCCACAGAAGAUUCCACCUCCAUUUUUAACAUUCUGUAUGGCUGUCGAGUCGACACCAAAGCAAAUGUGUCUCCAGACACCUCUCUCUCGUUGUCUCAGUCUUGUUGGCUUUAAUCAUCCUGUUUUCUCUGUUUUACGAAAGAAGUAAACAAAUUUCUAUUCAUCCACACGUGUGUCCCCAAAGCAAGGCAUAUGUGGACUGAAAGGUGGGCUGGGGCUUUGCUUCGAGAACGUGAGCGAAGAGCGUGUGAGUGCACGUUGCCUUUGGUGAUGCAUCAUUUAUAUUGACAUUAUCAGUGACACAGACAGAACAUUUUUAUGCCAGUUUGAGAAAAUACCAUCAUUCACAUUGAUAAUCAUAUUCCCCCCAGAUUUAGAUUAAUCAUUUCAAAGCUUUUCAUGUCUUUAGCAUGACCAUUAGCAUAAUGAUGAUAAUUUGUCCCUUUGAGUAACACCAAGCAUAAUUUAAAUUAACGUUAUUGUGUUGAGUGCAGUGCAACCCCAGGUGCUCAAGUAGCUUCCUUUUUUCAAAAAUGGCUUUUUACUUUUUAAAAUGAGAGGCAAGCAAGACGAUCUCAUUCCUAAAACCAACUUAAAAAAUAAAAGUGUUAAUAAAUAAGUGAAUUCCUAAUGUAAAAGUGCUUGCCGUAGCAACGUAAACUUGGGGACAAUUCUGUAGAGUCAUGCGAUUAGUGGUUUAGUGGUAGGAUUAAAAUUAGCCUCGGUAAAUUACCCUGGUGACAGAAAAGCAGAAUCUGUUAAUGGUUUCACAGGAAGAUUGGCUUAUCAGUUAUUUUCUAGGUUGAUGAAAGAUUAUGGGCUGCUAAGAAUUUGAACUUUAGAAAGUAAGGUUGAUUUUCCUAAUAUUUACAUAUUUUAAAGUAUAGGUAUUGAUUAAAAAGAAAGUUAUUACAGUUAGAAUUUGGGAUUUUAUAUGUGUGUGGGAGAUGAUUUACAAACCAGGUUUUUUGCUUAGCUGUGAACAUUAAGGGGGCCGUCGAGAGUGUGUGUUUUAGGCAAUCCUUAAAUCCCGUCCAGGGGAAUAGUAGACCAUUUUGGAAAGCAUUUUACAUGUUUUGGACCCACGAAAACUCCAUUUAGAUUCCUACAAGGUGGUAGGUGAUGAAACUGCACCUUCUUGGCCCGAGCGGGGUUAGGGCGGCCGCCAUUUUAGAGCACGGUGUUAUAUCGUUAGGAGUGUUACAUUGACUUGGUGUAAUGACCGUGAAGGAAAGCAUUUGCUUUCGUGAUUGUUUAUGUUUCUUUGUAAACUUACAUUAUUUGUAUUUGGGCUUGUUUUAGAAGGUUAAUAUAGACAAUCAUAUAUGUGUUAUAACUGCAGGAAACUUGGAGGUGAUUUUUGAGUGAAUCCUGACAUUUUACAGGUACUGAAAUGCAGAAAGAUUUAAUAACUGAGCCAAGGCCACAGGAAUGGUGCAGAGCUCAAAUCCAGGCGUCCUGAUUCCCAGCUUAGCCUUUUUCUCCAUACGCUGUGCUGAAUGCACAGAAUAAGGGGAGGUGAAAGUCCACUCUGAAAAGGAACUUGGUAAGCGUGUUGUCAUGCUGAGUUAGCACUGCCAAGUGUGGACCUGGCAAAUAACCAGGUGUUUAGGGCAGUGUAGGGAGAGCCCCCCUUCAGCUUUGCUUGGAUGCUUAGAGCUUGCUCCACAGAGAAGAAACAUGUUGAGUAAAUGUUUGCGUCUUUCCACGGGGAUGUCGUGCGAGUUGGGCACUGGACCAGUUGUUGCUGUCUGAGGCUGCUGUCACAUGGCAGCGCUCAAGGAGGAACGUGGAAAAUCUGGUCACCAAAGACCAGGCAGCUAUCUGCGCAGAUUCCCAGCCCCGCAGUGGGUGCCAGGAUACAGGUUUUCUUGCGAAACCCAAUGGUUAUCACCAAUAGUAACAUAUUUUUAUAAGAGAGUAAAUACAGAGUGUAAGUGACCAACGUGGGAUAUAGAAAAUCCUAAAAGAAAAAAGCCACCAAAAAAUCAUAGGGAAAGGGGUCGGAGAAGACCAGGUCAGUUCUGAUAGACGGCUGGGCCCUGAGACUCACCUUCUUAAGCCAGGAAGAUGAAAUGCGGGUGGGCCAGCUGACGGGGGACAUUUGGCACUCAUGGGUUCUCAGUGUGGUGCGGCAGAUGACCCGUGACAGACAGAUGCCGAUGACGGACAGAUGCUGAUGACGGACAGAUGCCGAGAGGGAGCUUCCCACAGGAGUGGGCAGGGAGGCGGCAGAGACAGAGUGGAUCAUGGCAGGUGCUUUCCUCUGAGCUCAGCUUUGGUGCCAGGGGACAAGAUGGCCACAAAGAGGAGGUGUUGGGGACCCCAGAGAGCUGAACCCAGGAAAGUGUGCAUUCUCCUCCUUUCUUUCCAAUGGUCAGGUUGGCUGGCUUGAGCUGUGUCUGCCCCGGGUUGCUGUCUGGACCUUUGCAGAUUAUUAAACACCUCCUGGAGGAGUCUCCACCCCGCCUGCCUUCUCCAGCAAAGCAGGCAGCUGGGCCAGGGAGCAGGUAGUUUUUCUUUGUUGUGCAAGAGCCGCUUAAGAAACAGUGGCCUUUUGCAUUCUCAACAUGAGCAAACGUAGCCAACACCCUAGAUUUCUUUUCUUAAGAGGAAAAAAAUUAGUAAAUUCAGAAUUUUUUUUCUUUUCUUAAGAAGAUAGUACUGAGUACUCUUCAUUAUUUACCCGAACCUAUAUACUAGGUGAUUUUGCUACCUUUCUAGACAUUUCUCAAAAUAGGACCAAUAUAAAUGAAGAAAUGCAAAGACUUAUUUAAUCAGUGUAGUCAUUUAUGGACUUCAUCCUGUAGGCCGUGGUGUGAGGAUUUUUGCAGGCUCGUUUGAGUAUCUGGUCAUUGAAAUCUCACUAUUUGUAUGUUGGUAAUAAUAGUUUGCUUGUUUCUGCCUAUUUCAUUGCAUGAGAGAAUGAAGUGUGCACGUAAGGUCACACGUUUGAUACAGACAGAUACUCUCUAAUUUACGACAGGGCUGCCUUCCCAGAAACCCAUCCUAAGUUGAAGAUACUUUUAAGUCGGAAAUGCGUUUAAUACCCUUCAGUCUACUGAACAUGGUAACAUAGCCUCACCUACCUUAAGUGCGCUUGGAAUGGGUAAAUGUUAGCCGACAGUUGGGCAGGAGCACCUGGCAGUGCAGGUUGCCAUGAAGUACCGACGUCCACCCUGGAGAUCGCGGGGCUGCCGCUGCCGGGCCUGUGGAGGGAGCAGCUCACUGCUUUCUGCUGACUGCCUGUGGCUUCCUCACCUGGUAAAGUUGAAAAAGUGUAAGUCAAACUUUCCUAAGUUGGGGACCAUCUACAGUAAAAUACAAACAAAAAUAAAGAACGGGCAAUGGAAUAAUAGGUCGCGAUGAAGGGAAAAGCUGGAUCACAUAUGUACGUCUUAGGAUUCCCUCCCGUUGGUAGAUGUGAACCAAAACUUAGGAUGUGAGCUUUCUGGCACCUAAAACAAAAAGCAAAACAUGGCCGUUGAUGUGUUGCACUGACUCUCAGGAAAAAAAGGCAUCAGUUCUCCCAUGAAGGAAAAGCUUCUUUUAGCAUUAGCGCUAAAGUCAACUUCUAAACGUUGACUUUAAUACUGGUUGUUUUAAUACAGGCUGUAUAUUCUUACAUAGACAGUGCCUUCAAUAACAUUCUUAAGGCAAAAGCUAUUGUAGCUUUUGGAAAGUAGUUCCUUGUAGCUACUUUGAUACAAAAAGCCAAGGGCAUAAAAACAAAAUAAAAGGUAUUGAGAGCUACUUUUUGAAUUACUAUGACAGUAAGAUGUAAGUUAUCAACAUUACUGUUUCCCAUUAAAUUAAUAGAAAUUUUAUUUUCAUUACUAAUGACUUAUGAACUUGAAUCAGAUUGGGCAAAUGCCUCAAUAACUAGUUCCCUAAAUAAAUAGCCCACCAGUACUCAUUUUCUUUCAACAAACAUUGAUCAAGUGCCUACUAUGAACAGAGCAUUAUUCCGAGUUCUUUAUAUGUGUUAUUUAAUAUGCACAGGUCUUAGGAAACAGGCAGUAAUUCCCAUCCCCUUUUACCCGAGAGGACACUGAGGCCUGCACAGGUGAGUAACUUCAUCAAAGUCCCACAGCCAGGUUAUUAAGCAGCUCACCUUUUGGGCCAUUCCCUUGAGUGUCCGACCCUGGUCAUGCUUGUUACCCUGUGUGGAGUUCAUUUCAUUUUGGUCCGAGCCAUUUGGGAUUAUGUAGCUUUAGAGAUGACACUAUGGGAGACCAGUGUCCCUCCACCCUUCCUCUUUCUAGAUGGCUGGGGUUUCUGAAGCAUCAUCCAAGAGGGGGUUGGGACAGGCUGUCUGCCUCUUUGGGGUCCCCAGCCUGUCUAUGGGCCUGCUCUGUUCUGAAAAUAAGCAACAAUUUUGAGUCAUCCAUCACAAAUGAGAAACUUAAGAGAGUGAUCUGAAGAGAAUUUGAUGCCAAAAAAAUUUCUGGGUCAGCUGUAGCCAUCCCAGUGAGCUGGUGGGACUUGGUCCCGUCCUGCCUCUGACCAGGCUCAGUGGCCUUGGAUCCUAGGUCAGCUCCUGUGCAGUUCCCAUGAAGCCCAGAGGGGGCUUGAGCCACACCCUCCUCAGCUCAGAAACCUGGGUCUGUAUUUGCAAAACUCCAGGGCAGGGGUCAGCAAACGUUUUCCCUAAAGGACCAGAUAGUAUUUGAUAGACCUGCCUCACAGCUUGAGAGCAGCCCGAGGCAGCCUGGCAGGGAAGAGAUGGACUUCAUGGGCACUUGACAUUUGAGUUCCAUGCCAUUCACAUGUCACAAAAUACUCUUCUUUUGAUUUUGUUUUUAAUCCCAACCAUUUUAAAAUGUAAAAACCAGCCGGGUGCGGUGGCCCACACCUGUAAUCCCAGCAUUUUGGGAGGCCGAGGUGGGCGGAUCACUUGAGGUCAGGAGUUUGAGACCAGCCUGGCCAACAUGGCAAAACCCCAUCUCUACUAAAAAUACAAAAUUAACUGAGCGUGGUGGCGGGUGCCUGUAAUCCCAGCUACUUGGGAGACUGAGGCAGGAGAAUUGCUUCAAUCCGGGAGAUGGAGGUUGUAGUGAGCUGAGAUCACACCACUGCACUCCAGUCUGGGCGACAGAGCAAGACUCCGUCUCAAAAAAAAAAAUAUAUGUGUGUGUGUGUGUGUGUGUGUGUGUGUGUAUGUGUAUAUGUGUGUGUGUAUAUAUAUGUAAAAACCAGCCUUAGCUCACUGGCUGUACAAAAACAGGUGGUGGGAAGAGUUUGGCCCGCGGGCCUGUAGUUCGCUAACCCAGCAUUCAAGGGCAGUUUUGCCCAAGAGAAGUACCAUGCACGCUAUGUCUAUCACUUUACGUUUUCUAGUGAUCACAUCGAGAGGUAAAAGGAAACACGUAAAAUUAAUGUUAAUGAUAGUUUUAUUUAAUCCAGUAUAUCCAAAAUCCAAAAUGUUAAACGUGUAGAUGACAAGAAUUACUACUAAGUUUUUUUUUGUUCUUUUUUUUUUUUUUUUUUUUUUUACACAAAAUCUUCAGUGCCCCAUGUGCAUUUUACCUUCCCAGCCCAUCCCAGUUUGGGCCAGCCCCACUUGGCAGCCUUAUAGGAUGGCAUAGCUCUAGGGGCGCCCCGCCACAAACCGCCGCCUGGUGCCAGGGUUGAGUUAGAAAUCUCCAGGCAGGUUCCUCUGUUUCUGAUUUCUGCUAUUUGUUUUCAAACCAGGACACUAAGGGGGAAGGUACAUUGCUUUAAAACUGUCUCUGGGGGAUCCCAGCAGUUUAAGGGGAAAGGGCUCUUUUUUAAUAACCUCAGGCCCUGUCCCAAGUGCCACAGUGGUGAAGUGUCAGGGUCCUGGGUGUGGAGGGGAGGCGUCUCUUCGGGAGACCACAGGGCAGCCAGGAGGCCAAGGGCCUGACCCUGCCAAUGUCUGCCCCUCUGCACACUCUUGCAACAGAGGGCCCCUGUAUUGGUAUUUCCCAUGUUCCCUGCACCCAGGUCUCCACUGGUGCAGCAUUUGAUAACUCAGAUUUAUUAGCUUCAGCAUUGUGGGUCUGCAGGAAGGAAUCUUGGUGUGGCUGUGAAUCUAGUUCCACAUGUGGUGUGACUUCUGGCCCGUUACGAACGCCUGUGCGUCUUCCCUCCAUCUGUGGGAUGAAAGGGGAAGCCAGCCUGCCCCAGGGGUUAGGAGAGGACCGUGCCCCAGGGACACCUUUGGACAAUGGGGAGCUGGAACCCUGUGCAAAGGAUCACUCACAGAGCAGGCAGAAUUGCAGAUGCAGACUGACUUGCCGGGAGAAUUUCAGAAAACAGAAGGAAAUCAUGAUGGAUUGAGUUUAUUCUUUUCCCGAACAAUUUCUGUUGUGGUUUGCUGAGAGAAUGUGGCCCGUGUUCACAGGGACGUUCUGUUCUUUAGCAGCAAGAGCUGGAACGACUGUUGACCAUUUUACCUGCCCUGUAGGUCCAAGUCAAGGCCCCUUUUAUUCAAACAUCCCGAAGUCAUGUGACUCUUAAGAUCGCACCAAUGGACUUGGUGGACAGACUGAGGUAUCCUGAUGAUGAUUGUUCCAGGUCUGUUCUGAGAAGGAACAAAAAGGUUUUCUCUUCCCCAGUGGAUCUUUUUUUUUUUUGGACAGAAUCUCACUCUUGUCACCCAGGCUGGAGUGCAGUGGCAUGAUCUCGGCUCACUGCAACCUUCGCCUCCCAGGUUCAAAUGAUUCUUGUGCCUCAGUCUCCCGAGUAGCUGGGAUUACAGGCGCACACAACCAUGCCCAGCUAAUUUUUGUAUUUUUAGUGGAGAUGGGGUUUUGCCAUGUUGGCCAGGCUGGUCUUGAACUCCUGACCUCAAGGGAUCUGCCUGUUUCGGCCUCUUACAGUGCCGGGAUUACAGGUCUGAGCCACCAUGCCCAGCCCCACAGUGGAUCUCUUAAGUGAAAAGCUGCAAAUGUAAGCAUUUUAAUAAACUUUGAUACAGAACUGAGAGUGUACUGAAAGUGUGUUUGAAAUGCACUCAUUUUUCUGCUUUGCUAGAAAAAGUUUUUCUGCUUUUGAAGUUUUGGAUCAUGAAUGUAUAUAUAUUCUCUAUGUCAUCUAAUAAUAAUUUUACAUUCAGCCUAUAAACUGUAAGGGAUUUGUUAUUCCUAUUUUUUGUAGAUUAAAAAAUUGUUUAUUUUAGAAAAGAGAUAAUUGUGAUAUAAUUCAUUUAGGUAGAUGUUAUUUGUAUUGUAUAUUAAACCUUAAACCUUUUUUUUCAUAAUUUGCUGCAUUUUAGUUUUGCCAACCUCUCAAUAUAAACAAGUUUACAAAACCUAGAAACUCUUAACUUUGCUUAGGGUUGAGGAAUACCUGGAGUGAAAACCCCAGACAAAGUUGAUUUAUUUCAUACAUCAUUAUUGUACUGGUAGAAUAGCAACAAAUGCCCUUCCUGUUGAAGAAUGAAUAUUUUAUUGAGAUGAUGGUUUUACAUACCUCUCCUCUCCGCAGUCUUCAUCGAUGAAUUUGUCACUCUCUUUAUGAAUCUGUCACUCUCUCAUUUGUCCUGAAAAUCUGAAAUAUAGUUGUUGGAGUAGAAGUUAGUACACUUUCUGCUCUCCACCAGAGUUUACAAAAACACUUUAAGUUAGGGGCUUUUCACUUAGGAGAUCCAUUCGUGGGAAAGAUAACCUCCUUUUCCCUUCAGAAUAGAUCUGGAACAAAGUGUAUUUCAUCAGCUGUUUUUAAGUAGGUCAUUUACAUAUAAUAAUUAAAAAAUGGAUAACAAUACUGGUUCAGAAAAGCUGUUUCUCAGAAGGAAGAGUGAAGUAACUCAAAGCAAACCAAACUCCUUUAAGAAGAUGCUUCUUAAAGCAUCUUCUUAAAGGAGAUGAGAAUUAAAUGCAGUGUAAUGAGUUUGCAUUCCUUCGUUUCAGCAGGUUUUUUUGUGUUGUUUGUGUCUUAUUCCCAUGCUAUUGGGAAUUACAGUGAGAUAAAAAGGAACCCUUUACAGUGGGUCAUUUUGUGAGUGCUUGAGAAUGUGUGGGGUGGUUUGGAAGCCAAGUGGAAGGGAAAAUGUAGGGGAUUUAAAGUAUAAAAUUGCAAGAGAAUCACAUUUUGUUGGUGUAUUUAAAAGUGCCACAAAGAAAGCACAAAAACCUGACCUUGUUUUUCCCCGGACAGAACGAAUCUCGCCUUUUGUCCCAUGUGUCUCAAGACUGCUGUCCAACUCAGUUUUGUCACAUUUUCAAGGCUAAGGCAGAGUUAAAUUGCUUCCUCAUUGUGGGGCUGGGUCCCGUUCUUGGAGGUGACACUUCAGGUUACCUGUUACUCCUGCUUAUGGAUCUGAUGUUCAGAGCAGCAAGUUUAUUACUUUCACGGAGGGUCAGUUUUCGUGCUUGCUAUAUUAGUCACUGAAAUGCUUCUUUUGAUAGGUCAGAUGAUAUUGAAACAAACUAGAAUUCUGUUUCCUGUCUGACUUGUGGAAUUGCAGUAUCAGUGUUCAGAAAACUUACCAGACUUUUGAACGUAAGAUCGACUAGCAUUCAAGUAGAAUUACAAAGUCCAAACGAUAUGACUCAGCUGGGAUAAAAAGUGCUGUUUUAUCUUUUUUCUGUUCCAGUGACUCAGCAAAAACAGUGCUUUGGACAUACGGAAAUGUAGGCAAACGAAUAUUUCUGCAUAAAGGGAAAAUGUAGACCUUUACUUUUAGGACGACUGUUUGUUAGUGGACCAGCCCAAAAUUCUUUUCAGAGUUUUGCAAAUCCACCUGAGUCUCCACAAGUGCAAUUUCAUCUGUGGGUUCUUCUCUUGAAAGUGAUUUAAGCCUCCGUAGCAAGUCACCCCGCACCGGCAUACAUCUGGGGGGCUCAAGAGCUUAGGCUGUUUCUAUCCAGUCAUGUGAAAUUUAUAGUUGUUCAGUUGCCUACGGUUCACCUAGUCAGGUGGGACCUCAGUAUUACAAUAAAUGAAGGUGUUCUGAUUAAAACAUCCCUUUCUUAGACAAACCAUGACUGGUUUUGGAGGUUAGUGGAAAACUGACACAAAACUACAAGCUUACGUUUAAUCGCUUGGCAGAAUUUCUUUCAUAUUCAUUUGACCACUGUUUAAUAUGCUUUAAGAUGUCUGAAGUUGGAGCUUAGAAUGUACACUGUGUCCUACUUUUAAAUGAGAGGAAUUCCAGUAGCUAAGACCAAUCCUAUUCCCUGUCCUGCAACUCCUGGAUGUGGACACUUUUUUUGCUGGGAAGUGAAUUGAUCUGAAUGUCAUUCUUCCAGGGAAUUAAUAUGAAGCUACCCAUUUUAAUUACUGAACCAGAAUAAAACAUUGACAACUGGCACUGAAGGCUUUACUCUUUGUUUAUCUUGUAUAAGGGGAUCAAGAUAGACAGAGACACUUUGCUUUUAAGACAUAUACGGUGAUUUUUCACAAAAUGGUGUGAACAUUUAGCACCUUUCUUUUCAUACUAUAAAAGGAGAUGAUGGUUGUGGAACUCACUGCAGAUAACUCAUUACUUGGUUUUCCAGCCACAAAUUUGUGUGGGUAAUUUAGUUAGAGCCAAAUACUUAGGGCAACAUUCUCCUUGCCCAAAUUAAACCAUUUCUUUUCAGAUAAUAGUACAAAGUGCAUAGUUUAUACACGACAAAGUCUUCAUCAUCUUGGCCAUCGAGAUAUUUACAGUCGAAAGAGGAAAUUGCAUUUUGAGGAAAAAGUGUGUGAGACGUUUCACAACAUGAGAGUAAGUUUAUUUUAUGGAAGCUACUAUUGAGCGCCUGCUCUAUGCCAGUCACUGUAUUAGGCAUUUAAAUACAUUCGCUUGGUGAAUGUAGUAAGAUCUUUAAAUAUAUACAUUUUAAAGAAUUUAAAAUGGUACAAUGUUCUGUGAGUUUUUCUGCAACUAAUUUUUUUUUAAUUUUGCGUAACAUUUCAGUGUAUUUGCUUUAAGGCAUGUGUAGGGUGCUGUUGUGUGUACACACCCUCAGUGAUUUCCAGAUGCCCAGUGCCCAGUGUGGCCAGAGCAUGGACCCACUGGCACAGAUUUGGUCUGUGAGCAGCCAGCAGGAGGUGCCCGUGUGUGCCAGCUGGCUGCUGCCCUGUGGAGCCGCCUUUCUUUGUCCUGUCUCCUGUUGGACAUUUGGGCUGCUAUCAGCUUUCUCUUAGCGUGCAGGGAACUUUACUAAUAUACGAGUUUGUGCACUUGUGGGAAUAUUUCUCUAGGAUAAGUUCCCCGAGGUGGAAUUUUGGGGAUGGAGGGGCAUUUUAAUUGACAGAUACUGCCAAAUUUACCAACAAAGAUAAAGUACCAUUUUACGUUCCCUGCAAAACUCAGUGCUUUCUCUUUGUCAGUGCUUGAUAUUAUCAGUCGUUUAAGUCUUGGCCAACUUAAUAGAGGAAAAUACCAUUGCAUUUAAAAAUCGUAAGUGAUUAUGAGGAUUUCUUAAUGUUUAUUGCUCAUUUUAUCUCUCUUGUGAAUCACCUGUUACUUCGUCACAUUAUCCAGUGAAGUUAUUCAUGAUUUGUUGAUUUAUAAGAACAUUUUGUUUAUUGGGGAUAAUAGUCUUUUGCUGAUGAGUUACAAAUAUCUCUUUGGGUAACUUGUUUUGUAUCUUCCGUCACAUAUGUUUUCCAGAUACAGAAACAUUCAGGUAGCCUAUAUAUGAGUUGUUUCUUAAAAUGUGUGAAAGAUUUCAGGUGUGGACUUGACUCAUCUCUCACAUUUGGGUAGGUGGAGGAGAGAGCUCUGGUUUCUUGCUUAAAUAUUGGUCUGUUUACUUUUUUUGUCCCUGAGUGAAUUUUGGACAGUUAGAUUUUAUUAGAAAAUUAUAUUUUUCAUCCAUAUUAACAAGUGUAUUAACCUAGAGUUUGAAAAACAUUGUAUGAUUUUUUAAAAUUUUCCUUCUGUCUGUGGUUAUUAGACCUAAUUCCUCCCAACCUCUUUUUUCUUCUUGAUUAGGCCAGCUAGUUAUUUAUCUCAUUCAUUGGGGUUAUCAUAGAGCCAAUUACUGAUUUUGUGUAUCAGUUUUACUGUAGUUUUUCUUAUUUAUUGUUACUCUUUAAAAUUCAAAUUUAAGGGUUUUAUUAUAUUUUUGUUACUGGUUGAAUUGAAUAUUUUUAAUUAUUGUAGCAAGUAAUUGAAUUUUAUUUUAGCUUUCUUGUGUACCAUAAAUUUUGACACUGGUACUUUGAAGAGAGUUUGCAGUUUCACUUUGAUUUCUUCUUUGUUUCAGGAGUUGUUACAGAGAGUUUAGAAUUUUCCAAAUGGCUGAACUUCUAUGAGUGUUGUUUUUGUUUUUGCUUGUUAAUUUUUAGUGUCAUGGUACUGUAUUAUGGAGCUCCUGGGACCUGUACUGUUUUGAAUUUAUGGAACUUUUAGAGCCUUCCUUGUGGUUAAUAUGGAGGCAUUUGAUGUUCUAUUGCCAAUUUAGCAAAAUAGCAAAUUGUGGAGUGUGAUACUCAUAUAUUAGAUAAGCCUUACUUUAUUUUUCAAGCUGUCUGUUUCUUACUACUUUUGCUUACUUAAUCUGCCAUGCUUACGAGAGAUUUGCCAAUUCUUCCAGAUCAUUUUUCUCUGUUUGUCUUUUCAGGUAUUCACUGUAGCUGUUUCUAAAUGCAUUUUAUUCUGUGUUUGUGUUAUUCUGUGUUAUUUGACUUAAAAGUGUAAUAUAACUACAGCUGGGGGAGGGGUGCUUUCCUGUAAUCCCACUUCUUGGGAGGCUGAGGCAGGAGGAUUGCUUGAGCCCAGGAGUUUGAGGCCAGCCUGGGCAACACAGAGUAAGACCCUGUCUCAAAAAGAAAGCCCCCCCCCCCCCCACACAAAAACAACCAACAACCCAGUGUUAGGACAAUUACAUCUUCUUUGUGAGUUCUACUUUACCCUUUAUGAUUAUAAGAUAGCUACUUUUUUUUUUUUUUGGAGAUGGAGUCUCACCCUGUUGCUCAGGCUGGAGUGCAGUGGUGCAAUCUCAGCUCACUGCAAGCUCCGCCUCCUGGGUUCACGCCGUCCUCUUGCCUCAGCUUCCCAAGUAGCUGGGACUACAGGCGCCCACCACCAAGCCUGGAUAAUUUUUUGUAUUUUUAGUAGAGACAGGGUUUCACCGUGUUAGCUAGGAUGGUCUCCAUCUCCUGACCUCGUGAUCCGCCCACCUUGGCCUCCCAAAGUGCUGUGAUUACAGGCGUGAGCCACCGCACCCAGCCAACUACUUUUGUUUAAUUGCCUUUUUUGACCACACAUUAAACUUUUAAUGGUAUAUUUUUUCCAUGUUGCUUUUGUUUGUACUUUUCUGAUAUAUUUUUCUCUACGUGUCCAGCUUUUCCGAGUUCCUCAGUCAUAGGUGUUUUUUUUUUUUUUUUUUUUUUUUGCAGAGAGCAAAUAGUCAAUUUAAUUUUUAACCCUAUCAUGGAGUCUUUUUUUAAAUAAGUGAGUUUAUUCCAUUAAUAUUUAUUUCUGAAACUGACUUACUUGGUCUUCUUUCCUAAUUAAAGAAAAAAAAAACUUUUGUGCUUCCUCGCUUUUUCUUCUUUUCUCUUUAUUGGAAUAUGAAUUAUAUUUCUUGUCCUUUAAUUAUUAAAAUCAGAAAGCAUAUAGAAAGCAUAUAAUGCUUUUGCUUCCACUAGUGGCGGUAUUUAUAAUGUUUUCUUAAAGCUGUAUUAAUGUAUCAACAUCAGUAGUAAUACAAUUUGACUUCCCCUUUGGGAAAGAAGUUAGAACACUUCUAUUACCUUCCUCUUCUUUCCCCAUCUCCUCCCUCUCCCCACAUUGCUAUUGUCAUUCCUUUUUUGGCUGUUGUUUUUUAGUCUAUUAGUGUUAAUUUUUAAUUUUUACAUGACAUAGUUUUUAUUUCAAGACAGGUAAGGAUCGCAUGUUUAUUUUAUGUGUAGAUCACAGUUAUUUGGAUGUAAUUCUAUUUAUAUUUAUUUCCUUGCUUACUGGAUUUAGUGAUCAUUGCCGGAUUUUAUUAUUGCUUUUUCUGCCUGUGAGGCCUUCAUUUGGAGCCAUCCUGUUUGACCGGAUGACCUUUCCAGGUUGCUCUUAAAGGACUCUGGUGAGGACACUCGUCCUUAUGGAGGAGCUAGCCUGAGCUAGGUGAGAAUCCAAGCAGCAGAAAAGUGGGUCAGAGCCCAGGAGAGCUAAGGAAAUUUCAUAUUGCUGAAGCCAGAGGUGCAUACACCUGUGUGUUCAUGCGUGUGAGCGCACGUGUCGCAAGUGCAUAUGUGUGUAAGUGUGCCUGAGUGUACGUGUAUAUACACACAUACAUGCAUAUGUGAAUAUACACACGUGUAAGUGCGCCUGUGUAUAGGUGCACGUUUGCAAGUGUGCCCGUGUAGUGAGCCUAUGCAAAUGCACACACACAUGUGCAAGUGUCUGUGCACAUGCCUGUCAGGGAUGGCAGGGGUGUCUGGGUGGUAGCCAAGAGCUGAUGUUUGAGAAGCCGUUAAAGACCACAUCAUCUUGACUGUGAAUUGUCUUGAGGAAUAUGGACUCCGUCCCAAGGGCAAUGGGAAGAGAUGUUGUGGAGGGUCCCUCAGCCAAUCUGCAGCAGGGAGGAAGCGUCACAGGCCAGGGACGCUGACCAAGGGACCGGCAGGAGGUUUCUGAAGGGAAGAUGGUUUGAUGGUUCAGAACAGGAAGAGGAUGGAGCUCUGGGCUAGAUUUGUGACUGAGAAACUGGAGCAGAGUGCCGUGAUUCUGACUUGGUUCAUGCUGGAAGGUCUAGAGUCUGUAAGACUUGGUCCAUCCACUGGAUGCGUUGAGAGGGAGGGAGGGUGCAGGGCAGCUGUUGUAUCCUGGGUAGGACCCUGCAGGGACACAGUCCUAGUGGGCGUGAUGUCCUGGAAUGAGACAUCCAGGGUAGACAGUUUGGGUGGGGCCGGAGUCCCAGAACAGCUUCCAUCUGCUGUGGGUGUCUUGGGGACACCUGCAGUAAGAUAGGGAUCUUAGGGUGUUUAGCCUCCACGGACUGGCAGCAUGACUGCAUGCUGGACCCGGCUCCUGGGGGAAGUCGGCUCCAAUUCUGGGAUCUCCCGUUCAGCGAUGUGACAGGAUCUAGCGUGACGGGAUCUAGUGAGGCCCCGACUGGUGCCUGGCUGAGGCCCAGCUGUCGUGUGUGGAGUGUUUCCACCAGUGGUGGCCUCUGGACACCAGAAAUGCUGUUCACAUGGGCCCACCGCAGGUCAGAGAACUUCUGAACUGGAAAAGGCCUCCCAAUUUGUCCAUUACAAAUGACACAUUUCACAGAUGGGAAAAACGAGGGCCAAAGAAGAGAAUGACCCAUCUAAGGCCACAUGUCUGACCAGAGAAAUGAGAGUUGGCCCAGGAAUCAGUCCGUGUCUGGGGUCGCUGCCCUCUCUUGCCAGGUGUUAGAGGUGAUUCAAGAGCUGCAGCAAUCCAUUCUGUCACCUUUUUCGGGAAGAAAGUAAGGCAGAAAAGUCCCUGAAAUAAUAUGUCUUUUUUUUUUUUUCCGUGUGGAGGAUGUGGAGGGUUUGCUCAGUAAGUAUGGUAAUCAUCUGAACGGAUAUGCCAGAUAUGCAUACUUUUAGAAUUAUUCCUGACAAGUUUUUCAUAAUACCAUCUUUAUCUGUGUUUCUUGUUUCUUCUGCCCAACAGAUUGGUGAGGAAUACUGUAAAUCAUAUUUUUGAUGUAGGUAAAAGAAAGUAUCUGAAAGGUGUUUUUAAAAAAUUAAUCCACUUACAAAAAUAUCUUUGAAGAAAGAAAACUGCCUAGGAAGGAGAAAGGAAUAGAAAAGAAAUUUAAAAAAUCAGGUUUUUGUGGAACUGUUUUUCUUUUUUCUUUUUCUCAGGCUCCCGAGUAGCUGGGACUACGGGCGCCUGCCACCAUGCCAGGCUAACUUUUGUUGCAUUUUUUAGUAGAGACGGGGUUUCCCUGUGUUAGCCAGGAUGGUCUUGAUCUCCUGACCUGGUGAUCCGCCCGCCUCGACCUCCCAAAGUGCUGGGAUUACAGGCGGUAGCCACCGCGCCCAGCCUUGUGGCACUGUUUUUAAGUGCAGGGCAAGCCUUACAGUAUGUAGGGAUUUAUAGAAAAUCAUAGAUAAGAAGUCCUUAAUGAAUUAGGGUAGAACUUCAGUGCUUUUGGCCAAGGGUGGUCGUUAAAUGUUUGUAACAAAAAUCAAAUGGAGUAAAAUUCUCAGAAUAAACCAGAGAGCACAGAAGAGGGUUCGUAUGGAAUUUCCAGUCAGGAAGAAGCAGACCAUUCCAAAGCUCAUUGAUAUAAGGGCUCCUUGGAUCAGAACAGUGCAGUGUCCGCUAAAUGUUGCAUGUAAGAUCACUUCAGCUUGGAAUUUCUUAAGCAGUUAGUGCAGAAAGAGUAGCUCUGUUAAAGCAUACUUGUGUUGGGUAGAAAUGUUCCCUUCAUGGAACUUUUCUAUAUAUAUAUGAAUUAGAAUUGUAUCCUGACCACUUGUGAUUUGUUCCAGAUCUAAGUUAAAAGUUGGGGGGAAAACGCCAAGCAAAGGGAAACUGCACAUUGGUUGGCUCAGAUAACUCAGCAGUUAACGUGAAUUGUCAAAGCCGGGUAAUCCACCAAUGGGCGGUUCCAAAUCUGAGAACGUGAAAACUGGCUCUCUCAUCUAGAAAAAUGUGUUUUGGUUUGUUUUGUUUUUAAACAGUUUAUGGAUUCUGGUGAUGACCUCUGACAUCCUUAUUUGGGAUAAUACCAUUUAAAGAUGAACAUAUUUCAUGCAGUUUUAACAGUAGAUUAUUUACUUAACAAUGCCUUAUAAAUAUUAUCUCAUUUGUAUUUUGUAAUGAUUUCCUGAGUACAAUUUUAAAGCAUUUCAAAUGAUUUUGAGCAUUUAAAACCUAUACUUUUUGUUUUGUGUUUUUUAUUGUGAUAAAAUAUAUGUAACAUAAAGUUUACCAUUUUAGCUAUUUUUUAAGUGUACAGUUCAGUGCCUGUAUUGGUUUUUUAUAAUUAAUGAAUAUUAGUUGAAAGACACAUGAGGCAGCUCUGUCUGCUUUUCUGAGUACAGUGGUUUAACCUUUCAGAUUCCAGGACUUUCUAACGGAAGAAGAUAAAAAUAGAAAAUGAAGUUUUGAUUUAAUCCCAACAUUAAAUUAUAUUUUUAAAAAUAUUAAACUUUUUGGUCAGAAGACUAAAGUUACCAUACUUUCUUUAAUCUAAAAAGUGAGUCUCCUCCCUUAUCCCAACCCGGUAAUUUUUAAUUUCUUCUUACACUGAAAGAAAGCUCUUUUAUCUUGAAUGCAGUAGUGGAAACUAUUAUUAGGUCUUUGGUUAUUUCAAUGUAGAAAGGAAAAUAUGUAACCUAAAAUCAUGAGUGCCUUCUUUUAACUGUCCAUUUUGUGGAAUGUAUACAUUCAGAGAUAUUUAUUAAAACUUAUUUUUAAAAAGCCCUCUAAAUAUAAAGAUAUAAUGAGUGUGGCUUUUUUAGUAAUAUAAAAAAUAGGACUGCAAAUCCUUAAUAAUCAUAUGUUUGGGGUGUAAUUUUGGACUGGUGAUUUCACCACACUGCACAGUUGACUAAUUUUAUAUUUUGCUGGGAGAAGGCAAAAACUUUCUUCCAGUAAAGGGAACAUUCGCACACCCUGAUUUGACUACCUCGGUUAUUUAUAUUCAGGCGUACAGAGCUAAACAUGUAGAAACAUCAUGACUUCAUUACAAAAUCCAAAACUAUUCAAGAAUGAACAUUAAAUGCCUUUAAAAUCGGGCUGGGAAGUUGGAGACAUUAGAACUCUUCAGACCUGGAGGCUCUCCCCAAGUGCUUCUUUGUAGCAGUGUGGUUUAGUGGUUCAGGACCUUCCAUUGUUGAAGGACAUAUAAUAUACAAUGGAGUGAUAAAUAAAGUCCUGGCAACAAACACUCUUUGAGGACUAAACAAGGAACUGAUGGGGAAGAUGGCUCAGCAUUUUAAGUUACUCUUCUCAAGUGACAGUUUUCAGGGGUGUCAAUUUUUUGGCUUCCCUCGGCCACAUUGGAAGAAGAGGAACUGUCUUGGACUACACAUAAAAGAUGCUAACACGGCCGGGCGCGUUGGCUCAUACCUGUAAUCACAACACUUUGGGAGGCCGAGGUGGGUAGAUCACUUGAGCUCAGGAGUUUGAGACCAGCCUGGCUGACAUGGCGAAACCUCGUCUCUACAAAAAAUAGAAAAAAAAUUAGCUGAGUGUGGUGGUGCACACCUGUAGUCCCAGCUACUAGGGAGGCCAAGGUGGGAGGAUCGCUUGAGCCCGGAAGGCCGAGGUUGCAGUGAGCCAAGGUUGCACCACUGCACUCCAGCCUGGGCGACAGUGAGACCCUGUCUCAAAAAAAAAAAAAAAAAAAGACACUAAUGAUGAGCCUAAAACAAAAAACAAAAAACAGCAAAAAACCUCAUAAUGUUUAAGAAAGGUUAUGAAUUUGUGUUGGGCUGCCGCGGGUUGGACAAGCUUGGACUUUAAAUUGUCCAGAGAGCGAGUGUGAUUGUUUUUCUUACUAAAAGAGCACGGGGCUGCUCCAAAUCACAAGUAUUGUAGGACACUGCCAAUCCUAAUUUUGAUAUCUCUAAUUUCAGAUAAACAUAAAAAACACAUUUCUGUAUACAUAGAGAGCAGAAGUUCUCUAUUUCUGAACCUUUUUGAUCCAUCAGAGCCAGAGAAUCUCCUGGGAUGCCUUGAGUGGCCUGAAGUGGUCAGUUCACAGAAUAGGCACGGGCUGGCUGGGGUGUGUUGGCUGCUGCAGGGAGUCCCGCAAGGCCGUCCGUCGCGUGCUGUCCGUAGGGAGGUCUGGAAUGCGCCGCAGCUACUCUUUGCUUGCAAGGCUGCCUGGGAUGACAGUGGGAGUUAGCAGUCAGCAGAUAGUUGAAGCACUCAUUUCUGUCCUUCGUUUAUUACUUAUAUGUAGCUGCCCUGAGCGGGAUGGGAUGCAUGUAGUUAUUCGAUAACUGGACUUGAAUUUAUUUGGUAAAAAUAACUCAGGAAUCGAACGGGCUUACAGUUUGAACAUGCCUGCAAAUGCAGGAAAUUGCUAAACUUCUGCUUUGAAAAUGAGGCAGCCCAUGUAGAUUGCAACAUGUUUUUGAGGUGUAGCCUUUGAGUGGGCUGGGGCUGUUGUCUUUCUCAAGAUCCCAGUUAGGAAGGAGCAGCAGGGACUCCCCUCUGGUUUGGACCUCCCCACCACCAGCCUCCGAAGCCUUGUCCCCUCCUUGACUGAGCACUUACUUGCAGCCUCCAGGAAAGCCCAGCACCUGUGGAUGCUGUAAUUCCAGCACUGCCCCCGAGGUGUGCUUAAUAUCUAGUUAGGGCGAGAGAGAUCUCAGGGCAGAGCGUUUGCCCAAAUCAUUUCCUCUCUGGGACAAGAGACACGCAGGACUUCCUGCCAGCCCAGAGGGGCUGUGAGCUGCAGGUUCCGAGAGACACGCAGGACUUCCUGCCAACCCAGAGGGGCUGUCAGCUGCAGGUUCCGAGAGACACGCAGGACUUCCUGCCAGCCCAGAGGGGCUGUGAGCUGCAGGUUCCGAGAGACACGCAGGACUUCCUGCCAACCCAGAAGGGCUGUGAGCUGCAGGUUCCGAGAGACACGCAGGACUUCCUGCCAGCCCAGAGGGGCUGUCAGCUGCAGGUUCAGCGAGGCCACGGCUGCCUCUGCCUGAUUUUACUUCCCAGAGGCCAGCGUCUCCUGGGUUUUGCCUCUCUGGGGCCCCCCUGCCUCCCAGGGCCCUUUGCCUGCACCUCUGGGUGGUCCUUCCCUGUGAGGCUGCAGAACCAGGGUCCUGCCCCAGGGCAUCCCUUCCCAUGUUUGCUCCCCACGUUCACCGCCCGUGGCAUCACCACCAUAGACUCCAGGUCCUGGUGAUACCCUGGUGGAGGGACUUCUGUGUCAUCCUGUCUCCUGUUGCAUCAGCUGUGCGUGUCCCAGCAGGGAUGGCCCUCGUGGCCCCUGUGCAUGUCCAGGGUCCCUUCUCUACUUUUCCAGCCCCCACUGUAGGCACGUGUCCCCACUGGGUGUCUUGCCUCACACCCAUCCCAGGCUUGGCAGGCAGGCACCACUGCGUCCUGUGUGCCACGCUGUCUAGAGAGCCUGUCCACAGAGUGCCUUUCUCCUUGACUAGAUCUCCUGGAGAUGCGCGGCCCCGGCACCUGCAUAGAGCACUUGGGUCCGGCCGUGCCAGCCAAGUAGCCUCUUUGGUGUCCCCGCCAUCCCACCUGGCUUGGUCCUUGUGGGCCUCACAGAUGCUGGUAGCCUGGUGAGCGUGCAGAGCGUCGGCCUCCGUGCCAGCAUCCCGUCCACGUGGCAGCAUGGGUGCACCAUUAUGGGAGUGGGGAACUGACAGAGAGACCUGAAUGCUGUUCUCAAGGGGCAGGAGGUCCUGAGACUCCCAAGGGAACGGAGUCUCUGUUGCAAGAGCCCUCCCUGUGCCCCUGCCUGCCUGGAGCAGUGGAGAGCGAGGUGGCCGCCCGGGUGGGAUGGAGUCCGUCUGUGAGAAGCACCCUAGGAGUAAACCCAGUAAUUAGUGUCGUAAAUCAAAUCUCUCCCGGAGCCUGAAUUAACGUCACUCCUAAGGGAACGUGAUGGUUUCCAGUAUGGCUUAGACCGUCACCCAGGGACAUUAGAAGUAGGGGGAAGAAACAGUUGAUCAUCAGAAAAUGCAUCGAGAGGACUGCUUGGGGCCUCUUUAAAUUGAAAAUGGUGUGUCUUUGCCCAGCAGAAGUUUGAACUGGGAAGUGUGUUGAACAGAAGGGUUUGGGCGCAGUCUAGCUGUUCCUGGGAUUUCGCCUUUGCUGUCCCAGGAGCCCAUCUGGGAGCCUGUGCUGCGCUCGGGUCCUUCUCCCAAGUCCCUGCUGGUCCCUGAUGGCUCCUUGGUCCAUCUCUGUUUUCGUGACCAUCACACUUCUGAGGAGGACUGGCCGGGUGUUUUGUGGAACCCAUAAGCUCCAGGUCCUGGUGACGUCCUGGUGCAGGGACUUCUGUGCCCUCAGUUUGGGUUCUUGCGUGUUUUCUGAUUGGUUUAGCCCAGGGUUAUCGUUCCCGGGAGGAAGAUAACCUUCUCCCGCAGGGAGAGGCCCUUCUCAUCGCAGCACAUCAGGGGUUGGUCUUGUAAACAUUUACUCGUAUUUUCGCCUCUUUCCAGCCCUGCCUUUGUCUGUUACUGGUUAAUACAUCUGAAAGUAAAGGUAUAAAGUUUCUUCCCUGUCUGUCCCUCCAUCCUGGAGCAUUUCUCCCGUGUGCUGUCCAAGGACGCCGCAGGGUCAGCCUUUCUCAGACACAGAUUGGCCCCCUUGGCCCAAAGGAAAUAGAUUUUUAAAAAGGCCUCUUUCUCCUUUGAGUUUCCUUGACUAGAGAAUCUCUCCUCUUCUGCUGUCGAAGAGUAAGAUCUUUUCUGUUUCUUCUGCCCUGUUCCACCUGUAACUGCCAAAUCUGAAGCUGGUGUCCAGGGGCAGGAAAGCAUCUCUGGAUGUGCAUAACCCGAAACCUUGGUCUCAACCCCUGUGGCCUGUCGAAGAGGGGAAACUAAGCCAGAAAAUAGCUUGUGCUUAGUUUAAAAAACUGACACAUGUUGAAGACACGAUGUCCAGCAGAUAGUGUGGAUGACCACGCCAUUUUGGUGUACGAUGCAUGCCAGCCUUGAGCUGCGUGGCGAGCCCUGGGCCCUGGCACCUCUGGAGCCUCUCUCCUCUGGCGGCUCCCCUCGAGGUUGCCUGAAGGUGAGGAGGGUGCAGCUGCCCUCAUCGGAUGCACGGCUGUAUCCCUGGGGUCGCAUUCCAGUAGUUUCUCCGCAUCACUAAAGAUACUGGGGCUCUAGCAUCCAUUCCCACUUGGGCUCCUCCAACUGCGUAAGGCUCCCAUGAUACAUCCCCCACCCUUCAAAAGAUGCCUUGACUAAAUCAUGAAAAAAAGGAGACUUUUUAACCUUUCCAUAAGUGAGAUGGCCAGGCUGGGGUGCCAGAGAGGCCCUGCAAGUCCAGGAGGCCACUGUCCCCAUCUGAAAUGGCCAGGCUGGGGGUGCCAGGGAGGCCUUGCAAGUCCAGGAGGCCACUGUCCCCGUCUGAAAUGACAAGGCUGGGGGUGCCAGAGAGGCCCUGCAAGUCCAGGAGGCCACUGUCCCCAUCUGAAAUGGCCAGGCUGGGGGUGCCAGGGAGGCCCUGCAAGUCCAGGAGCCACUGUCCCCUAUCACUGCGCAUCACCCUGCCUUUCCACAUAGGUCUGGGGGCUCUGCACCUUUGUCUCCAUGACUCUUGGGGUUUCCCAGUGAUGGUUCUGAGAUUUCUGAAUGCCAGCUUGAGACAGCAAAGGCCCCAGUCAUGCCAAGCUAUGUGUGAGUCCCACUUUCUGUUUUUGAGACUGAGUCUCACUCUGUCGCCCAGCCUGGAGUGCAGUGGUAUGAUCUCGACUCACUGCAACCUGCACCUCCUGGGUUCAAGCGAUUCUUCUACCUCAGCCUCCCGAGUGACUGGGACUACAGGCACACGCCACCACGUGCCACGUUUUUAAUGUACCUUUAGUACAUUAAAAAUUUUUAAAGUACUAAAAUUUUUUUUUGUAUUUUUAGUACAGACGGGGUUUUACCAUGUUGGCCAGGCUGGUCUUGAACUCCUGACCUCAAGUGAUCCACCCACCUCAGCCUCCCAAAGUGCCGGGAUGACAGGUGUGAGCACCCGCGCCCGGCCUUGAGUCCCACUUCUGAGACUGUAGAUGGAGAAACAUGGCGUGGUGCCGUAAAGAACGGGAAGUGAUGGGGAGAUCUUGUUUCGGUGGAUCUUCUUCUGUCUUUUUUCCUUUUGAAAAGUGUGUGUAGUUCAGGACUGAGAACAUAAGCUUUCGAGCACUGCUUAUUGCUCAGGCAGUGGGAAUAGUUUAUUAUGAAUACUUUGCUAGUGUCUGUUUUAAAGCUUGCUGUCAAAUCGCUUUGGAAUGACUUUCAAGUCUAGUGAGAGCUGUGCCACACCCUGAAACAUCUGGGGAUUCCGUGGUCCCAGGUAUAAGUGGGACACCGAUUUCAGUGGGCACGUCUGCGUUGCGGUCACAGACUGGCUCCCUAGUACCCUAGUGUGUUUUGUAAACGCAGAUGCUGCGGAGGAGGUGAGUAGGUGGCGCCCCACAGACCCAUCCCCAAGAAGAGCGAGAGCCACCCAGGGGCCUGGCAUUUCUGGCGGUCGGCAGUGUGAUGCGCACACCAAGCGCAGUCCAUGCCAGGAGCUCAGGGCAUAUGCAUAGCAGGUGUUCCCUGGUGACAUUUUGAUAGGCUGGAUUGACAACUAAAUGCAGAUUGUUCCGCUGCUACAGUUAGGCGGCGUCCUGGUUACCUUCGCUGCUGCGUUUGUGCUGUGACUGUUGAAUGCUUCUCCUGCUCCUGGCUGCCCCUCACAGAUGUGGGAAGUCCUAUUAGAAACCACACUGUGUGGGAUUUUCCCAGCAGCCCCACUUGGGGUGAUUUAAUUCAUUCUGAAAAUACCUACGGUAGCCCCAAAACGUCCUUGGGCAUUGUUUUAAUUUUUCUUAAAGAGAAGCAGUGGCAAAUGGUUCUUAAAAACAUAAUUAGAUGAAUACUAAACUUUUCCUCAUUUCAGAAUCUGAGAGAGGCCGAGUGGAGUUCGGUCCUUCUCUGAACACUUUUAGCUGAGAGUACCAGCAUCCAACUGGGAGCGUUGUCAUUGCAUUUCCACAUUCCCAGGAAAGCCCAGGUAGGUGCAGUUGGAUCACCUUCCUGUCAAUCCGUCUGACUUCUGUUUCACAAACCUGGAAUUUCAAUCAAGCUUAAAACAACAGUUAUUACUUUAUGGUGUAGGGUCGCUUUUCUUGGCAUAGCUAGAAAAAUGUAAAAUGAUGGUAAAUAGAAGAAAAAUAAUUAAACCAGAGCACAUAACUGGGAAGCCGCCUCUGUGGGCUACUUUGAUGAGGACAUAGGGAUCACAGUGUGAAUGAGGUUUUCUGCUGAAAAACAGCCAGUGUAAGCUGAUCGUAGAACUUGGUGCUCCUGGGGUGGGGGGUCCAUUCCUUUUUAUGAUCUGGAAAACUAUUGGCUCGAGGAUAUUAGCUUGCAUAUGAGUAAGACCCACUUUCUUUUCUUGCCCAAGUUUGCACAGCUUAUUACAGUUGGGCGAUGUUUUUGGGCAGACAGCUCUCUUCUCUUCUGGGAGGUGCCGGAGCAGAGCUGCCUAACGCAGUGAUGGAAUUGUGUGGUGCAGGCUUCAUCUGCGUCCGCACGGGGGCAGGUUUCGGUUGUUACCAGGCAGGUCUUUAAUGAGGUGGACCGCUAAUCUCUCUGCUGAGACCUGCCCUGACGGCGAUGUUUCUAAACUAAAGGGGCGUUGGAGGAGUGCCUGUGUUGGACUGUAGGUCCCUUGUGGGAACAGGAAGAUGUGGUGUGAACUGUCUUGUGUUGUUCUUCAGUAAUCGAUUGGGUCAUCAUUUGAUUAAAGUAGUGAAGUGGUUUUCUUGGGAUUCCUACAAAGCCGUCUCUGAGUUUUGCAAAUCUGGAGCUGCUGGUGCAAGUCCUGCCCGCUCCCCACUGUGAUGGGGUGGCCUCUGGCGUGGAAGUGUGUCCCGUGGGCAUGGUCACCAGCGCUCAUCGGCGGAGGCUGGAAACACGCUUCUGUGGCAGAAACACUUUGAAAAAAAGGUAGAUGCUGGAAGAAUAUACAAAAUGUCAUAUUAAUUUAAAAGGUAACCGGAUGUGGGAAGGGUGGGAGCCAGGGCCCGCACGCUUGAUAUCCGGGCUUGGGCAAGAUCAUCCCCACAGAGUCACAGGAGGAGGGCGGAGCGGUUUCCCCACAUACCACACGCCUGCAGGGCUGGACGCCGCACCCUUCCCAUCCAGGUGAGGCUGCCCAGGGUUUCUCGCCUGCUAGCUGGUCCGGCCCAUGGCGGGCACUCGGGGGAUACCUGUUGACCAUCUGAUGAGACCUGGGCCCCUCGCCUGUUGGCGACAAGCCUCAAGCUGGUUCCCGUGCGGUCCCUGCAUAUUUUCGGUACUGCUGAAUCUUGGAUGGAGACCUGAAGAGGAAGGGAUCUUGAAUUUGUCAAGCGCCCACUGUGUGCCAGGCGCCCAUUUUAAGCACCCGAUGUAUGUUUUCUGAUUUUACGUUUGGAUGGCAAGAUUGCAAAACGUUUGUGUCCUAUAAAUGAAUUUCUGACAAUUGCAGAAGUUAUAGGUGACAAAUGACUCCUUCCACCCCCAAAUUUCCUCUAAAGGCCACAUUAAAUAGGGUGAUCCAGGGCUUCUCAAGUGGUGUAGCCCAACAGGUUGGUCCCAGGUGUGUGGAGACGCUGGUCCCCUGGGCCCUCUUGGUCAGGGAGGCAGCAGAGGGUGGGGAAGUGGCAUGUGCCACAGGGCUCGGAGGAAGCCAACAUGUUUUUCACAGUGCCUGUUGCGGCCAUGGUGAUCGGUGUUCUGUUAGACGAGACACUGGCCUCACCAUUACAUGGUCAGUGUGCAGUGAUGACGGAGUGUCCAGGAGGAGCUUGGUUUAGGCAGAUAAGUCAGCCCCGUUCAGUAUGUUGUUAUUUUUAUUUAUUUAUUUAUUUUUUGAGAUGGAGUCAGGCUCUGUCGCCCAGGUUGGAGUGCAGUGGCAUGAUCUCAGCUCACUGCAACCUCCGGCUCCCGGGUUCAAGCGAUUGUCCUGCCUCAGCCUCCCAAGUAGCUGGGAUUACAGGCAUGCGCCACCACGCCCGGCUAAUUUUUUUUUGUAGUUUUAGUAGAGAUGAGGUUUCACCGUGUUGGCCAGGCUGGUCUCCCUGACCUCAAUUGAUCCACUUGCCUCGGGUUCCUAAAGUCCUGGGAUUACAGGCGUGAGCCACCGUGGCGGGCAGUAUGUUGUUUAAAAAGGCCCUUCUAUUACUUCUGGAAAAACAAAGGGUUAAGUAAUUACCCGCCAUGAACAAGCGAGGCGAUCAUGUGGCAUGGCUUCUCCGGUUUGGGAGUUUUGAUUCUUAUUUUCACUGUAGCUUUUUGCAAGUGAUCUCUCUCUCGGGGUGUGCUCUGACAUGACUUGCACAAUUCCAGAACCUCUCUAGCCCUGAACAGAAGCAGAGUAGAGCUGUCUACUUGUCUUUCAUGAGCAACUGGGCUCGUUGAAAAAGGGAGGAAAACAGGAUCGAUCAGCCACCUUCCUCCCAGUUUUUUUACUGGUCAGUGGCCGACUUGCCAGCUGCUCAGGAUGGUGUGGCCUCUUGCUUUGUGUUGAUUUGGGGUCUUAGAGGUUCAUAGGUGAUGGCCACAGUGGUCGCUUUUGUAGCCCCGGAUGUUACUUUGUAUUUAGAUUGUACCCCUUUUAUUGGAAGGUCAAGGAAUGUUCUGACAACUCCAGAAUGCUCAUUCCAGGCACCAGAGAGCGGGGGCCUGGAAGGUGGUAACAGGGAGGCAGGAAGACAGGGAAUGGGCUCACAGCCUUGUCGAGGGAUGUGGCUCACAGCUUUGACCCUCAGCGUCCUCGUCUGUGAAAUGAGGGUGGCAUCGCAGAGACGGAGGAGGGCCCUGGACGGUGAGUGCAGGCAGAGGUGCCUCCUGUGCUCUGUGCCAGGAUGAGGAUUUAUGAUUGCUAACAGCACUAGGAGUCAUCGGAGUUCCGCAUGUUUCAACCUUCGGGUGAGUGUCGCCCCUUGCUGUGUUUGGUAGGCACAUUCCAACAGAACGAGUCCUGGUCCAGAAAUGCAGUGCGGUGUUUUCUGGGCAUUCUUCCCAUUUGUUAGUGGAAGCAUUCCUUGGCGUAUGUUGAUAGUGGUUAAAAGACUGCAUUCUAGUGCAGUGGACAUGAUUCAUUAUUUGGGACUGGUGAGACAGACCUGCCCGAUGCCAAGGAGGCUGCCUACGUAAAGACCCCACCCGGCGUUUCCUUAUCAUCAGUAUGUUCCUUCUUGUGCCUGCCGGAUCGCCUGUUCUUAGCCUGCCUGCCACCGUCUAACCUCGUCUCCGGGGGCCUGCAGUUGGCCCUGAAUCCUCCCGCGUUGUGAUGGGAUACCCACUGUGCUCCAGGAGCAGUGCCUGGUGUAGCGUGAGGCUUCCGGUUCUACCUCCUGCCCUGCCACUUCCUGAAGCCCCGCAUCAGGUCCAGGGGAGGCUGGGCCACUCUGACUCGGGCUGUGGAGCUGCUGGACAUUUAAAGGCUUGGUGUUGAGAAGUGUUGCUGUUGGCAUCAUGGCAGACAGUGCUGGAAUACAUUCCGAGGGAGGCGACGCGGUGCCCGAUGGGGUGCACACGGCCGCCACGUCCUGAAUGGCACAAAUCCUGGGCUGAGCUCAGGGCCAGCUUGGCACGCGAGGCCUCCCUGGCCGGCAGUGGAGGGCCAGAGUUUUCUCCCACGAAGGAAGCUAGGACGGCUGUCCUCAGAGAGCUUGGGUGCCUGUGGGAGGGCUCAAUGAUGUUGAGUGGAUGGUGGCCACGGGUCAGGGCUGUCACCGGCCCAGGAUUUCCCGAGCUGGCACUGGGUCCAGUGUGCCUCCAGCAGUGACCGUGCAUGGAGGAGAAGCCGAAGCUCGGGGCAGGGAGAGAGCGCCCUAUGCACAGGAGAGGGGCAGCAGGUGGGCCCGGCGCCCCGUUACUGCUGCAGCGUCUGGCUCUGUGCGAAGCUGGUAAUCCAGGCACAUGGGCACGAGUGUUGCUGGUAGAUUGUUGGAAGUGGACAUGCGUGUUUGCCUCCAGGUGCUGGCUGCCAGCUGCUGCGCCCCCCAUGUAGAAGGUGCACCUCCUGGGAGCAGGCACGUCUUUUGGCUCUUCUGACCAUGGAGAGAUAGGACGGUCCCUGCAGCCCGCGCGACAGAAAGCUGUGCCGCCACCACCGGCCGCGCCCGUCCUUCGGAUGGAUCGCAACAGAGAGGCCGAGAUGGAGCUGAGGCGAGGCCCCAGCCCCACCAGGGCCGGCCGGGGCCACGAGGUGGAUGGGGACAAGGCUACCUGCCACACCUGCUGCAUCUGCGGCAAGAGCUUCCCCUUCCAGAGCUCGCUUUCGCAGCACAUGCGCAAGCACACGGGCGAGAAGCCCUACAAGUGUCCCUACUGCGACCACCGGGCUUCCCAGAAGGGCAACCUGAAGAUUCACAUCCGGAGCCACCGCACGGGGACUCUGAUUCAGGGACACGAGCCGGAGGCGGGCGAGGCGCCGCUGGGUGAGAUGCGCGCCUCCGAGGGCCUGGACGCCUGCGCCAGCCCCACCAAGAGCGCCUCGGCCUGCAACCGGCUGCUGAACGGGGCCUCGCAGGCCGACGGCGCCAGGGUCCUGAACGGGGCCUCGCAGGCCGACAGCGGCAGAGUCCUGCUGCGGAGCAGCAAGAAGGGGGCAGAGGGGUCCGCAUGCGCCCCGGGGGAGGCCAAGGCAGCGGUCCAGUGCUCCUUCUGCAAGAGCCAGUUCGAGCGUAAGAAGGACCUGGAGCUGCACGUGCACCAGGCGCACAAGCCGUUCAAGUGCAGGCUGUGCAGCUACGCGACGCUGCGGGAGGAGUCGCUGCUGAGCCACAUCGAGAGGGACCACAUCACCGCGCAGGGGCCCGGCAGCGGCGAGGCCUGCGUGGAGAACGGCAAGCCCGAGCUGAGCCCCGGGGAGUUCCCGUGCGAGGUGUGUGGCCAGGCCUUCAGCCAGACCUGGUUCCUGAAGGCGCACAUGAAGAAGCACCGGGGCUCCUUCGACCACGGCUGCCACAUCUGCGGCCGUAGGUUCAAGGAGCCCUGGUUCCUCAAGAACCACAUGAAGGCGCACGGCCCCAAGACGGGCAGCAAGAACAGGCCCAAGAGUGAGCUGGACCCCAUCGCCACCAUCAACAACGUGGUCCAGGAGGAGGUGAUCGUCGCCGGCCUGAGCCUCUACGAGGUCUGCGCCAAGUGCGGGAACCUGUUUACAAACCUGGACAGCUUGAACGCCCACAAUGCCAUCCACCGCAGAGUCGAGGCCAGCCGCACGCGCGCCCCGGCCGAGGAGGGGGCGGAGGGGCCCUCGGACACCAAGCAGUUCUUCCUCCAGUGCCUGAACCUGAGGCCGUCGGCGGCCGGCGACUCGUGCCCUGGCACGCAGGCCGGACGGCGGGUGGCUGAGCUGGACCCGGUCAACAGCUACCAGGCCUGGCAGCUGGCCACGCGGGGUAAGGUGGCCGAGCCGGCCGAGUACCUCAAGUACGGGGCCUGGGACGAGGCGCUGGCCGGGGACGUGGCCUUCGACAAGGACAGGCGCGAGUACGUCCUGGUGAGCCAGGAGAAGCGCAAGCGUGAGCAGGAUGCACCAGCCGCGCAGGGGCCCCCGCGGAAGCGCGCGAGCGGGCCUGGGGACCCCGCGCCCGCCGGCCACCUCGAUCCCCGCUCGGCCGCGCGCCCCAACCGCAGGGCCGCAGCCACCACCGGCCAGGGCAAGUCCUCCGAGUGCUUCGAGUGCGGCAAGAUCUUCCGCACCUAUCAUCAGAUGGUGCUGCACUCACGCGUGCAUCGCCGCGCGCGCCGCGAGAGGGACAGUGACGGGGACAGGGCGGCGCGGGCCCGCUGCGGAUCACUCAGUGAGGGUGACUCGGCCUCCCAGCCCAGCAGCCCUGGCUCCGCCUGUGCCGCUGCUGACUCCCCGGGCUCUGGCCUGGCCGACGAGGCUGCCGAAGACAGUGGUGAGGAGGGCGCCCCUGAACCUGCACCAGGGGGACAGCCGCGCCGCUGCUGCUUUUCCGAAGAGGUGACUUCGACCGAGCUCUCCAGUGGAGACCAGAGUCACAAGAUGGGAGAUAACGCCUCGGAAAGAGACACCGGCGAGUCCAAGGCAGGGAUCGCAGCUUCUGUGUCCAUACUUGAAAACAGUAGCAGAGAGACUUCUAGAAGGCAAGAGCAGCACAGAUUUUCUAUGGACUUAAAGAUGCCAGCAUUUCACCCCAAGCAGGAGGUGCCCGUCCCUGGUGAUGGUGUGGAGUUCCCUUCCAGUACGGGAGCGGAGGGCCAGACGGGUCACCCUGCAGAAAAGCUGUCCGAUUUGCACAACAAGGAACACUCUGGGGGAGGGAAGCGGGCGCUGGCCCCAGACCUCAUGCCGCUAGAUUUAAGUGCGAGGUCGACGCGGGAUGACCCCAGCAAUAAGGAGACGGCCUCCUCCCUGCAGGCGGCUUUAGUCGUUCACCCGUGUCCUUACUGCAGCCACAAGACCUACUACCCCGAGGUCCUGUGGAUGCACAAACGCAUCUGGCACCGCGUCAGCUGCAACUCCGUGGCUCCCCCGUGGAUUCAGCCCAAUGGUUACAAAAGCAUCAGAAGCAAUUUGGUUUUCCUUUCCCGGAGCGGACGCACGGGCCCCCCGCCUGCCCUCGGUGGCAAAGAAUGCCAGCCUUUGCUCCUUGCUCGGUUCACCCGCACUCAGGUGCCAGGGGGGAUGCCGGGGUCCAAAAGUGGCUCUUCUCCCCUGGGAGUGGUCACAAAAGCCGCUAGCAUGCCUAAGAAUAAGGAGAGCCAUUCCGGAGGUCCCUGCGCUCUGUGGGCGCCCGGCCCUGACGGGUAUCGACAGACCAAACCUUGUCACGGCCAGGAGCCACAUGGCGCGGCCACACAGGGGCCCCUGGCCAAGCCCAGGCAGGAGGCUAGCUCCAAACCGGUGCCUGCCCCGGGUGGCGGGGGCUUCAGCAGGAGCGCCACCCCUACGCCCACCGUCAUCGCCCGGGCUGGCGCGCAGCCCUCGGCCAAUAGCAAGCCUGUGGAGAAGUUUGGGGUCCCCCCAGCGGGGGCUGGCUUUGCCCCCACAAAUAAGCACAGUGCCCCGGACUCCCUGAAAGCCAAAUUCAGUGCUCAGCCUCAGGGUCCACCUCCUGCAAAGGGCGAAGGGGGCGCUCCUCCUCUACCUCCCCGCGAGCCCCCCUCGAAGGCAGCCCAGGAGCUGAGGACUCUGGCCACCUGUGCUGCGGGGUCCAGGGGCGACGCGGCCUUGCAGGCCCAGCCCGGCGUGGCUGGGGCGCCCCCCGUCCUACACUCCAUCAAACAGGAGCCGGUGGCCGAGGGGCAUGAGAAGCGCCUGGACAUCCUCAACAUCUUUAAGACGUACAUUCCAAAGGACUUUGCGACCCUCUACCAGGGAUGGGGUGUCAGCGGCCCUGGGUUGGAGCACAGAGGGACACUCCGGACGCAGGCCCGGCCAGGAGAGUUCGUCUGCAUCGAGUGCGGAAAGAGCUUCCACCAGCCCGGCCACCUCAGGGCCCACAUGCGGGCACACUCAGUGGUGUUUGAGUCCGAUGGGCCUCGGGGUUCUGAAGUUCAUACCACCUCCGCAGACGCCCCCAAACAAGGGAGAGACCAUUCUAACACAGGUACCGUCCAGACAGUGCCUCUGAGAAAGGGAACCUAAAGGCGUGUUUCCGACGCACCCCAGGUCCCCGUAACGGCCAUUAGCAGUACCCUCACGAUGUCCCAGCAGCCUCCCACCUGUGACCUGGCCGCUCCAUGGAAGAACAGCCGGGGAACUCCUGAGCAGACACCUCACAUCCCGAGCCGCUGCGCUGGAGUGGAAACUGAAGGCAGAUGCCUCUCCUUGUUAAACGUUCAGAAAUAAAUGAAGAUGCUAUAUUCUAGAAAUACAUGUAGAUACUAUAUACGCAUUUACGUGCUCAUCGUCCAUAGUCCCAUAUUUUCUUAUAAUAAACAGUAGUACUGGCAGGCACAGUAGGGGCACAAGGCAUCUGUCUUAUUCAAGACAAGUUUGAGACACUGGAAAAAAAGAUACUUGUUGUGUGUGUUGGACAGAGUGGCGAGGCUGAGCACUGUCACAGGGGCCUCCCAUGUUAAGAGGGACUGUGGGGAUGAUGUCAGAACAAGACGUGGUGGAUUUGAGGUUGAUCGAGUAUUAAUACUACUGCCUCUCCUUGUCUUAGUGGGUAUUUAAAAUAGUAAAUAAGAGAGAGGAAGGAGGUGACGUUCAGGUGCUGUGGGAAGCAGGCUUGGCGGAGGGGUAUGAUGAUGAGACCCUCAUUGUUCACUGGCUCCAUCGCACUCCUCCCUGGGGCCGUGUGCCUGUUCCAUUCUUCCCACCAUUCGAACUGAGCGAAUCUGGCAAAGGAGACACGUCUGUGGGAAUGCGUAGAUUCCGCCUCGGAAGAGAGCUAGCGCAACACUAAGAAAAGCAGGCUUCUUGUUUAUUCUCAGGACCUUUUUGUAACAGGGCUACAUUCUGCAAACUGCUUACAAAGGAAGACUAUACGUCUUAACAAAUUAUUUAGCCACUGAGUCCUCCCGAUUCGGACCUGUUUUAGUAAUGGCAGAAGAAUCCCUGAGCAGGUUCAGGUGCCCUAGAUGACUAGGGUGCUGAGCUCUGGCGCCUUCUGUCCCCACUCUUUGCCUCCCCGCCCCUUCCCUGAGCCACCCCAGCAAGUGGGUGUCUUUUCUCCCUGGGCCUGGUGACCUCCACAGGAUGAGUGACUUUGUUCAUAAAGGGUGGGGAUCACCAGCCCCUUGGGUGGGGGACGGCUUCAUAUACCUCUUCCUCAGUAAUGCAAAUGCGAGUUUUUGUGGUGGGGGUUAAGGCCCAUAACAAAGGAUCUUAAACCAUGCAGUGUACGCAAUUGAAAUGGUAUUCCACAGAUAUAAAUAUUUUCUUUUCCCAUUGCCGUGACACUAUGUGUGAUGGUAAUAUUUCUGAGAGUUUCAGAUUUUUGCACAUAUGAUUUUAUGCAUUAUCAAAAGUUACUGCUGCCUUGAAUGAAAAUGUUCUGUGAAAUUUUUUGCAAAAGCUUUACUAGGUUUUUUUUUAAUUGUGAAAUUUUGUAAAGGCAGGAAAUGGAUUAAAACGAGCAUGCUAAAUAUAUUUUUCAAAAAAGCAAUAAUUUUACAUGUACAGAAAUUAUCCUAACCUUUAAUACUGGCGAGAGCAACAGUUUACUUAAUACGGUAAUGGACUAGUGCAGUUUUUGUAGACAGUGGGCUUCUGAUACAAAGUCUUGUUUAAACACAGACACACACACACACAAACACACACACACACCCUAAAGUGUGGGUUUCCUGUUCUAAUGAUUUGUUGAAUAUUAUUAUAUUAUUAUUAUUAUUAUUAUUAUUAUUGUUAUUGUUAUUAGUAAUGUUUGGUUCUGGAUUCUACUUGUUACUGAGUUUAAAUUACUUGACGGUUCAGGUUACUUUGCAACACUUUCAAACGAUGCAAUGUAACUGGCUAGCUUAUAUAUAUAUAUAUAUAUAUAUAUAUAUAUAUUUUUUUUUUUUUUUACUUAUUUUUUUCUGAUAUUCUUACACCAGAUAUGUACGAAAAUGAUCUGUCCUGUUGGUGUAAUUAGGAAUGUCCAUGCAGAUACAGUUAAACAACUGUAAUUGACUGUUCUGUAAAGUUAUUUUGGGCAAAGUUGCGGAGACACAUUCCUCUGUCCACCUAAGAAAUCAGAAGACUCUUCUGUUGAUUUAUGUUUAAUCAUUUCAGUAGUUUCCCCACAGUGAUCAUUUCUGCAUUUUCUGGCUUUUGUUUUCUUGGCUGAAAGUGAAUGGUGACUGUUAGGAAUGUCAGGGACUAGUGACCCAGUCCUGUUUCUCUGUGUUUUAGUUAUUAAAAAGAAAUUCUGUACCCAAAGUGACACGAAAGUGUAGUCUACAUUUUUACUGUUUCAGAAGCGGCAUGGAAAAGUGCAGUUGGCCUUUGGAGCUGGAAGUGUCUUGCUGGUGAGGCUCCAUCCUGGAGGCUCUGGUGGGGAGUGGGCUGGCGCUGGGGCCCUGCCGGCCGCGUGCUGGAUCCUUCCUGGCUUGCAGGAGAGCAGGCGUGGAGGACAGUCAGCUUGCGGGGCCGCGCAGGGUGCACAGAGUGCAGGAGGAAGGUUUUCACCCAGUUAAACAGACUGGGGAGCCCCCCCAAGAACGCCAUCCCUUGAGGCCAGCUGUGGGCAGGCCUGGAUGUGUGGUCCCUUCCUUCCACCCAUCGUCAGUAUUGUGUUGGUUUGUUAAUUUGUUGAUUUGGUCAUAGUAUUUAAUAUGAUUUGUGUUUCCUUAUUUAUUUAGCCACCGUUUUGAUUGCCUUUUUUUUUCCGAAUGGUAAUUUCUGCAUGAUACACUUCUGUACGUUGUCUUCUGACUGUUACAGACUUUCUACUACCUCUCCCGAUCUGCUGUUUCCUUGUUUCUUAACAGGAUUUUUUACAGUGUUGCGUCUAAUGUAACUUAGACAAUAAAGGGUUUGGUUGUCUACACUGCAGCUUCUCGGUGUCUCUCCCCUGCUUUCCGCUCGCUGCUUCCCGCUCUGCCCCUGCUGGGGCCUGGCUGCACCCUGGCCUGCCUUCCUAUACUCUCCUGUUUCCUGCUCAUAUCUCUUCCUCAUUUUUGCGUUCAAAUAACACACAGCUAAUGAGCUUCUAAAAAUCUUUUCAGGUUGUUCACUUGUAUUCCUUAAUUUGAAGAAUGAAUAUUUAAAUUCUCUCAAAAGUCAGAUAUUGAGGAUCUUCUCUGGGAAAUUGGCCACUGUACCUGCCCACCUUUCUGCCUGGUUCCCUGGAAGGUCUUAUUGUCAUCUUAGACGGACAGAUUUCAUUCUCAGCACCAUACAGAUUUGGCUUCAAAGCCAGGUGAAUUUUGCCUUUGAGGCUCUGAAAAGUAUUAAGUGUUUUAAGAGGUCCCCCAAUAUUUACUUAUUUAUUUUUUAAACCAAGAAAGACACUGGUUCCCUGAAAAGCAGGUGCUUCAGGAAGUAGCAAUUGGGAGUUGCAUACAGUUACUUCGUCAGAGAAAGGAGCGCCCAGUAUGACAGGCCCCCACCCCUGAUCCGGCCACUGUGCACAGGUCGCUGAGGGUGUGAGAACACCUCUGCAGGGGCUCCGGCACAUGUGGGUUUCAUCGUCUCACACUCCUUCAGGCUGCAGGGGUUGAGUGCAGAAAGGGCAAGCUUCAUCUCCAUGGUGCCUCUCCAGGCUGGCAACUCUGGUCGGCCUCUGUUCUUUGGACAGAGAGGGUGUAGGUUACAGGGUCAGUAGGGAUGCUUUCUGGAUCAAAGAAAGUGGGUGUAGUGCUUAGUCUGUUGUGUGGAAGAGGGCACCUCCUGGGCUUUCGUGGCUGGAGACUGUCUACCAACAUUCCUUCCUUCAAACUAGACAAACCCUCCUCUGCCACCCCCAGCAAAUUCUCAGAGGUUUCCAAGCUGUAGAAAAAGGAAGGAAGGAAGGACGGCAUUCACAUAGCUUUACUUUCUGCUUCAAAAUGUCUUAAGUAGCAUAUGUUGUUUUACUGCUUUUAACUUUGGUGAGUUCUAAUUUCAGAACGUUUUGUUCACUGAGCAAAAAAACAGAUGAAACAACCACAGGCCAGGACUUCAAGUGAGGAGGACGCCUUUGUUUGCCGUGGUUGGUGGGAGCACACGCCGGAGCCCGGUAACGUGCCUGUGGGAGUGACCAAGGGCCACCCGCCCAAGGGAAAAUGUUCAUUCUUCAUCAGCUUUGCUAAUUCUGCUUUGAGGCAGUAAAAUGCAAAAGACCAUAGAAUUUGUAUUUCUUUUUUUAAAAUACAAUUUAUAACAUUAUAUUUUGUACUCUUUAUAUUAGAAUUUGUAACUAGAUUGAUGUAUUUAACUAUUUCUGAAAAAGUAAUUCAAUGUUUUAGUUGUGUGAUAAAAAUAUUUAGAUAAAACAUAUUCAUUCUAUUGGAAUUUGAAAUAAAUAAAAACAUCUUGGAGUUCUGAGAUUUGUAAGACAUUUUUCCCCAAUUUCAGAGGGUGGCGUAAAUCGUUUGACAGCCCGCUUUGGUCUGUGGUUAUUUAUUUUUGUUGGCUGAACAUAAACCAAAGUGUUAAUGCUCUUUAUUUAUGGAAGAGUUUUAGGGUAAUUCACAAGAUCGUUCAUCUGAACAGAUGCCCAGAUGGCCCGAGUGGUUUUUUUCCAACUCUUUUGUGGACUCGAGGACAUACAGUUUUUUAAUGGAGACGCUGUGUUUUUCUCAUUUUCUUUCACAGCACACAUGUUAUUUCCCCACUGAAUACACCCACUGUUCUUACCCUUGCACUGUCACCCAUACAGGACGCACAGGGAUGGACGCGGACGGAAUUCUGACUCAGCCACACCUGGAGGAAAUUAUUGUGUCAAAAAUGUGGGGACACAAGGGCUGGCACUGUGGUUUGCAAUGGUUUACUGAUGAGACAGCAAAAAUGAGACAGGACCAUCAGAUGCAAUAAAGAUUCUAAUUUAAAAAGA